AGGAGAGCGGGCUUCGGGCACUUGACAUGGCGGCAGUGGCGGCGACUGCAGCAGCGAAGGGGAAUGGGGGCGGCGGUGGCAGGGCCGGGGCCGGGGACGCCAGCGGCACGCGGAAGAAGAAGGGCCCGGGGCCCCUGGCCACGGCGUACCUGGUCAUCUACAAUGUGGUGAUGACAGCCGGGUGGCUGGUUAUAGCGGUUGGUCUGGUCCGAGCAUACCUGGCUAAGGGUAGCUACCAUAGCCUUUAUUAUUCAAUUGAAAAGCCUUUGAAAUUCUUUCAAACUGGAGCCUUAUUGGAGAUUUUACAUUGUGCUAUAGGAAUUGUUCCAUCUUCUGUUGUCCUGACUUCUUUCCAGGUGAUGUCAAGAGUUUUUCUAAUAUGGGCAGUAACACAUAGCGUCAAAGAGGUACAGAGUGAAGACAGUGUCCUCCUGUUUGUUAUUGCAUGGACGAUCACGGAAAUCAUCCGUUACUCCUUUUAUACAUUCAGUCUAUUAAACCAUCUGCCUUACCUCAUCAAAUGGGCCAGGUACACACUUUUCAUUGUGCUGUACCCAAUGGGAGUGUCAGGAGAACUGCUCACAAUAUAUGCAGCUCUGCCCUUUGUCAGACAAGCUGGCCUAUAUUCCAUCAGUUUACCCAACAAAUACAAUUUCUCUUUUGACUACUAUGCAUUCCUGAUUCUAAUAAUGAUCUCCUACAUUCCAAGUUAAAUCAGACAGGGUUGGACUUCUCCUCAUUGCAUGGCAUCAUCGGAAUGAAUCACCCUAACAAAGCGACAUGCUUGUGUCCCUCUGUGGAAAAUUGCAUUUCAUGCAUUGUGAGAAAAAAACUACAUCCAGAUUUCAUGUGAGUGUUUAUCUUGCAGAAAUUCUUGGAUACAGUUCUGCUUCAUGAUUCAUUUUCCACUCUUUAUUCAUGUUGAGUCCUCUCUAGUGCUGGAAUCAUAGCGACCAGAGGCCAUCUCUCUUCAAAUGUAAAAAGUGGUUGAUUUUCAAACAGAUGAUAAAUGUGAAAUCAUCUAAACUACUAAGUAAUAAAAAUUAACUGGUAGUUUAUCACCUUUCUAAUUUUGUUUUUUUUUUUUAGAGUUUCAUUUUCCAGUCUCUAGAGCAGCAGUUCACAGUUGCAGUUUUACCACACCCGGAGUAACUAACACAUAUUAUCCCAGUGGGCACCACAGGCUUUAUUUGAAUUCACCAUAGUCAAAUGAAUAGGAGAUAUGUACCAUAUUGGGUGACUGGGAAAGGGGCAGGGAGGUUUUUAUGAAAUCAGAUCCAUAACAAGCUGCUUCCACACUGACAAAAAUCUAGGCGUUCUUACCUGAGAGUUCCUGCAAGACUUCCAACCUCUCUAGGAAGCAGGGCUUCCUUCCAGGAACCACUCCCCAGGGCAGCCUCCAUCUGUCUGCAUGUUUGUCUCUUUAUGCUCUGGUAGCCAACCAGUGCUGAGCUUUGCCUCUUCCUUCUGAGCUCUUGGUGUAGUGGCAGUGCCUGGGUACCACACGCAGCCUCCAUGAUGAUAGCGUUCCUGAGGGAAACCCACUCCUGUGAGCUUUUCAUCUUGGUCUUGAAAGAGAUAGAGGAAAGAGAAAACACUGACCCCAGAGCCAGCUGUCUUUUAGAGCAGCAGUCCCCACAACCUUUUUGGCAUCAGGGACCGGUUUCAUGGAAGACAGCUUUUCCCUGGGCGGUGGAGGGGAUGGUUUCAGGAUGAAACUGUUCUACCUUAGAUCAUCAGGCAUUAGAUUCUCAUAAGAAACAUAUAACCUAGAUCCCUUGAAUGUGCAGUUUACAACAGGGUUCACACUUCUAUGAGAAUCUAAAGCCACUGCUGGUCUGACAGGAGGCAGAGCUCAGGCAGUAAUGCUCAUUUGCCCACCACUCACCUCCUGCUGUGCAGCUCUGUUCCAACAGGUGGCGGUUGGGGACCCCUCUUUCAGAGAGUAGGGAAGGACUCUCCUCCCAACAGAAGUCUGCUUUCUUUACCUUAAGUAAUUCCCCCUUGCAGUCUCAGCCUCCUUUUGGUAAGAGAACUUGGCUCAGUUAAAGUCUAACAUAAUUUCUUUUUCUAAGGCAGCUAACCUCUUGUAGACCGGAGAAAAGGGUGGAUCUCAAAUAAUGAUUAAAAGAUUCCCUGCAAACCAUUGACUCCUCACCCAGGUUCAAGAUGGCACACAGACUACCUCUCCUGAUGCGAGUCACCCUGGUGCCUGCUGGCCUCACUGUGCUGUGGCCUGAGCCAGCAGCUCUGGAUGUUCUCAGUGGUUCAGGUUGUUACUGUUGAGGCCAGAGUGUACAGUUCAUUCUGGCCAGCUGCACAUUUCCAACUUUCCAAAGCUUUGUAUUUAUCAGAAGAAAAUGCAGAAUUAGGAGAGGUUGCUGUUGACAUGCAGUCUCCUUUACCAAAUUUGGUUUUCUUUCUAAACAAGGUAGCGUUCUUUUAAUCUUUAGUGGCAAGUUGAUGAUACACAUGUAUUAUAUAAAGUAACACCUCCUUUUCAUGGGCCUCAUCUGUUGUUGCGUUGUUGCACACAUAGCCUAAAUUGUGGCUCAUGAGGCUUGACCCCAGGAGUUUCCUCAUAUUGGGGUGCCCUGGCCAGGUGCUCCUCUCCUGUUCUGCUGUAGUUGCAAUAUAUACAGGAUUAGUACAACACAGUCCCUGCAGGACUCAGUAGAUGUCUAAGGCCUGUUUACAUUCCACCCCCAAAUUGGUGAAAAUUGGUUAUGGUGGAGGGAGCCAAAAAAGGGCAAGAUACAUUGAUGAGGGGUGAGGACCUGGAGAAGCUGGCGCUUUCCAGGUUGUCAGUGACUGUAACCACACCUCUGAUUUUUAGAGAAACCAAGGAGACUUGGCCCAGGCAGAGAGCAUAUCUGGUGCUGUCGUCCUCCACAGUUCUCUCCCCAGAGGGGAAGAGAGCCCCAAGAGGGCUGGCCAUCUUCUUAAAGAAAGGAGGGCCCAGCAGCACCCACACCCCCCUCGUCCCCAACACACAGGGACUGUCACACACACGUGCCCAGCAGUGUCCCCAUUCUGUGUUCCCUGAAUUGGGACAGCAGAAGGUGGAAUUCUCAAUAGCCUGUUGUCGGGUUGAGGGGUUUUUUCAGUGCUAUUCCUCAGUGUAGCUCAUGUUGUUAAAAGUGGCAGCCGUGCAUCUGAAAAGCUUUCAGUCUCAUGGUCGGGUUCAGUCUGAACAUGUAGGUGAUUCAGAUGGAGACAGAAUCAUAGUUCUGGUCAGCCAGAAGCCACUGCCUGAACUGUGGAGAAUAGGCCAGACACCCUAGGCCCUUGGCCUCCCAUCCACAUUCCUUUCUCUGGGUACUGAGGAAUCUCUGGGAGAUGUAAAGGAGUGAAAGUGCCAUCAUCUGACCCUUCUGAUAGGUGGCAGGCCCUGCCCAUGGAAAUGAAGGUCUGCGUGGCCAUCUUCUUCCUUGAACUGCCACCAAGGGCUUAAUGCAUGACUUCCAGGUCAUUCUCCUUCCCCGGGCCCUCUGAACCAGCUGUGAGACUGCAGCCACCCACUAUGGGGUUGUGUGAACACAAAUGCAACCAGUGGGAAGGUCUUGUGCAUGCCCAGCUCACAGAUUCCCUUCAUUACAGUAAAUCUAUAGAAAUGGGACUGGCCCCACAUUUUUAAAUGAUUACCAUUAACAUUCCUAAUGGUUUAAUUAUAUCUUUACUUCCAGUUUUUAGAUUAUAGAGCUUGUCAGAUUUUCUGGCUUUCGUGCCAAAAUAGUUCUCUGCCUGUCGAAUUAUAUGCUUAAGUGGGGUCUUUUCUGUGAACGACGUCCUGCCUGGCAGUAGCAAUGGCGUGGAUGGCAGCCCUGUUCCACGUGCUGCCUCCUCUGCAGGUUAGCAGAUCUUUGUCACACACGCACUGGUGUCCCGGCGUACUUUGGGAGGAUCAUUUGAAAUCUGGCCAGCUUGGAACCCAUUUAAAAAGGAAGAAACUUGUCAGGAGAGAGUUGGGAGUAGUAGAAAUUAUCUUCCAAAAAAUAUUCGUGACAGUAUAAAAAAGAGAGACUGGGCUGGGCUUGGUAGCUCAUGCCUAUAGUCCUAGCACUUUGGGAGGCUGAGGCGGGCACACCCCUUGACCCCAGGGGUUCCAGACAAGCCUGGGCAACGUAGGAGAUCUCAUCUCUACAAAAAAUUCAAAUUAGUUGGGUGUGAAGUGGUGUGCACCUGUAGUCCCAGCUACUCAGGAGGCUGAGUGGGGAGGAUUGACUGAGCCCAGGAGGUCCAGACCAUGAGCCAAGAUCACACCACUGCAUACCAGCCUGGGUGACAAAGUAAGACUCUGUCUAAAAAAAUAAUAACAAUAAAAUAGAGAUUGGAGCUGUUGGAGAGAUGAGGAGAGGAAGGAUAUUGUACAACAAAGAGCAUUUUACCUGGAGUUGUUUACACACAGUAACCUUGUGAAGGCCAGGUGGCUCAAAGUGGUAUUUCCUAGCAGGGACACUAUAGGCAUUUUGGGUGGGAUACUUCUUAGUAGUGGGUACUGUCAUGCAUUAUGGCAUGUUUUAGCAUCCCUGGUCUCAUAUGCCAAAUGCCAGUAACCUUUCCCUUUCUCCCUUAUUUCCAAAUAGUCAAACUAUCGAAAUAGUUCCAAAUAGUUCCGAGGGAGGCAGUACUAUCCCAUUCAUUUGAGAACCAGUGCUUUCUAAAGUAUUCUACAAAAUGACCAAGAACAGAAGAAUCCCCAGUGCCUAAGACACUGGCUUGCUUUUCAUAAGGCCUUUUUUUUUUUUUUUUAACAUCCAAACCUGGCUUAGUUGUGUUCAAAGCAAAUGUUGUGGCAUUCCUCCUCCUCCUCAAGUCUUUACCCGAAACUACUUCCCAAGAGAGGUUGCUCUUCCCAAAGAAUCACCUGCCCUGGGACCAUAUGGGGCUAGGCUGAGGGUCAGGAGCCAAGAGCCUGGUCCCAACUCUGUCUGUGGCUUACUGUGAGACCCUAGGCAAGUUGCUUACCCUCUCUGGGGCUCAAAUUCUUCCUCUUUGAAAUAGGAAUAAUAACUUCAUCACUAGAAUUCUUCACCUGGUUGUUGUGAAGUUAAUCAGAAUAAAUGUGGAGAUAAUACAUGAAUGAGCGUACAGAAUAUUAUUUGGCUGUUCUGUGGCAUCGAUAUAGGUCAUGAUAGUGACAAUAGUGUCUGUCAUUGUAUUCCACACCACUUCUUCCCUCAGCUAAAGCAGGAAAAGAAAGGAGGUAAGUCUCUCUGUGUUUUUUCUUCCUUUCCCCAAGCCCACUUUGUUACCUUCCUUGGUUGCUGGAUGAGAAAUUAGUCAGAGGGUCAGAGAGGACCUCAACUUCAUAUGCUUUAAAUAGAGCAUAUGCAAUUUUAAACCAUCCUCUUAACCAAUUUUUCUUUUCUUUUCAGUUUUUCCCCAGUUAUACUUCCACAUGAUACACCAGAGAAGAAAGAUCCUUUCUCAUACUGAAGAACACAAGAAAUUUGAAUAGUUCCUGCUUUCUGCACCUCCCACCAAAACAAACUUUUCAAUGAUCAAAAAAUGCUGCAGAUUUUUUGAGUUCCCAAUACGUUUCAUAGAAAAUAAGUAAGAACUAUUUUUAAAAUAUUCAAACAAAACUAAAACAAAAAUCCAGUGUCACAUGGGCCUGAGAUUUUAUUUUAGAAAAAGGUUGUUACAUAAAACACCCUGGCCAGUUCAUUUCAGCAUGCUCUUUCAACCAGAAGUUCUUAAUAUUUAUGAUGGCACUAGAAAGGGAUUUGGCAUUUUAUGUCCUUCUGUGUCCUUCAUGUAUCUGAUCAAUGAAGACCUGUAACACUAAGUACUUGAGAGUUACAGUCUGAAUAAUGAAGUCGUACCAGCUGAAUAGCCCAGCUUGCAGUAUAGUUAUGUUUCAGUCUGCAGUGUGUUUAGCAUUCCCUUGUCAAAGUGCUUGACUGCAUGCUGGAAACUUUGUAUUUUUGAAGCGGCAAACUCUGUUCUCUGGAAUGCUCUGAAGUUAUGGCUGGGACCUAUCCCCUCACAUCUAAUGAAUGAAUUAUAAAAUGUAUAUGUCUAUGAAGCUUCGGGGUAGUGCCUGUAAUCAGAAAACAACUUAGAACCCUUUUGUUUGUUUCCAAUUGAGUCAUUACUGCCUGCCACUAAGAAACGUGCUUGAAUCUAAUAAGUAUGUGUGUACCGUAAAGAAUAUAUCUUAUCUGGAGCUCAGCCUCAAUCAUGUCUUAACAAAAUGACAGGUCUCAGAAAGGGGGAGCUCAAUAGCUCAAAAGUGACAAGUCCUUUUCACAGCACCAUUCUCAGAACACCUCUGAGUAACGUGUUUGCCAGUAGCUAUUCUCACUGAUGCACUGAUGGCCCUGAAGAAGCGGAUCCAGUCACAUAGGAAAGGAGGCUGUGUUAGUGAAAGCACAUGGAAGGUGUUGCUUUAGAAAGGUAGUCAGGAAAAACAUUCAGGAAUAGAUUUAUACACCAUUAUUGUUUUAUUUUUAAAUUUUCAUUCACUCUUCUGUUUGGAUACUUUUGCUAAUUAACUUCCUAUGUUAAUUUCCACCAAGCUAUAAGUCCAUAGUCAGUAAAACAUUCCCCUUGGGCUGUCAUGAGCUAAAAGCAGUGUCAUCUCCGCAUGUUGGAGCAGCCAAGAAAUAGUUUGGUACUACCGACAUUGUCUAAUCCAUGUCACAUCCUCAUACAAUUUAAUUGCUCAACCAUGCAUUUAAAACUCCUCAAGAAAGGAUUGGUACUGCAACUGUAGGUAAACUGAAAAAAAAUAAGAAAGAAAGAGUUGGAUGAAAAUGUGAAAGCCCAAGUUUAGAUGUGCAUUAAGUAUUAAAUAGCACAGUAUCUUCUUCAUGGAGCCUUUUUUCCUCCCCCAUCCCCUGCAGCUGCCUUUUUUUGGGGGCAGGGUGGGGGUUGAUGUUGAACUUUAAGAGUUUAAAAGUUUAGCUUAUUGAGUAGUUGUCAUUUAAAAUAUAAUUGCGAAUAUCAGAAAACUCAUACUGGAAAACUAAAUUUUUUUUUUCUCUUGAGACGGAGUCUCGCUCUGUUGCCCAGGCUGGAGUGCAGUGGCGCGAUCUCAGCUCACUGCAAGCUCCACCUCCCGGGUUCACGCCAUCCUCCUGCCUCAGCCUCCUGAGUAGCUGGGACUACAGGUGCCUGCCACCACACCCAGCUAAUUUUUUUUGUAUUUUUAGUAGAGACGGGGUUUCACCGUGUUAGCCAGGAUGGUCUUGAUCUCCUGACCUCGUGAUCCACCCGCCUCAGCCUCCCAAAGUGCUGGGAUUGCAGGCAUGAGCCACUGCACCCAACCCCUGGAAAACUAAAUUUUUAAGUGCUUAUUUUUAUAGAAGUUUGAAAAUUUAAUGCAGGCAGGUGUGUAAUAAAUUAUUUUUGAAUUGAACAUUAAAAUUCUGCUUCUUAAAGUCAGCACUCAACUUGGACAUGUUGAAAUUAGAAUCUAUUCUUGUAUUUGAUAGACAAAAUAUGUGGGAAAGAUUUUUUGCAUGACUUUUCUCUCAUUUUAUUCUUCCAUAAUGUAUUUCUACUAUAAAAUAGAAUCAACUUGGGUUAUAUUUGUCAUUUACUUUGUUCUGUUAGAUUUUUUCAGUUGUUUUUGGAAAAAUUCUAGAAAUCAGGAUGAAAAAUGCAGCUUUUCCAGGGUUGCUGGACUGGGGGUUUUAUUUGGGCCUCCUUAUUAUAAUUUGUCACUACUUAUAAAAAACAUUCUGUUGCAAACAGUGGUGUUGCAUUGAAUUGAACUUUGGCAAUGAGAACACAGCACACAGCUCCCUUUUCAAAAAGGGUCUCAACCCCAGUGUGUAUUUUUGUACAUCAACAUUUAGAAUACUUAUGGCAGAUAAGUAAGGCAUGUCACUGUGUCCUUCAGUAACCUCUCUCAGUAACUGGUUUCUUUAUCCCUAACAUGAAUUCAUUUCUCCUUUGAAGUCAUUUAUUAUUUUAUAAAUUGAGAACAACCACACCACCAAAUGUCACACCUUCUUAUAAAGUGUGAACAAGGAAGGUCAUGUUUUUGUGGGUAUUUUGUCAGACUUAGAGGUUUCAUUUCAGGGCAUAGUCAAAGGCAUCAUCCUCCCAACUACCCACUUGAUUAUGUAUUUCAGAUCCCUCCGUGGGGGCCUUCUUCUGACAGAGAAUUCUUUGAGGUCCGCAGUAGUGCUUUUGUCAGCACAGACUGCUAAUCUACAUCUUGCUGCGUUCUGUUUGCUGAGGUUGGGCUUAUUCAUUUAACACAUACCAACCAUUAUCCAGAGGCACCAUGGAGAGUUAGUCAUGGAAUAAAGCACUGUCCUUGCAGAUGAAAAAAGUCUCCAGAGCAGACUUCUGACAGGAAAGGUUUAGAUGCUGGAGAGUUGAAGAGGUGUAAGAAGAGAUCGUGCCCUCAUUUUUCACUUAUUUUUUUGGUUAUUCAUUUAUAAUAAAAGGUUGGCAUUGAUAUGGUACAACCUGCAAAUUACUUGCAGUUCUGAGUUUCAGAUAAAACAUUAUAAAACAUUAAAUUCAAUACAUACUGCUCCUUUGAAAUUUGGGUAAAAAAUUGUACAACCGUAUAUAUAGUCAUUUUUGUAUUUUUUCUAUGUUGUGAAAACCAAAAUUGUAAUUUUAUAAGUCUUUGAUUCACUAAAAUUAUAUAAUUUAAAUGUAUUUUUUGUAUAUUUAGAAAUAAGGAGUCCAGAGACUACGCUUAACUUUCUAUGCAUGCAUUUGAAAGCUGUUUUUACCUGAUAAUGUAGUAAUAAGUUGUAUUCAUAAAAUACUGAUCUGUGUUGCAUUUCAAAAUAAACUGGUGUGUGCUCUGCCUGGAUUUGAAA